AGUGUGUUCUGACGGAGCCGAAGUACAGAAACCAUAUUUACAGGUAAGAGCGAAAAAUAAAAAAAAAGAAAAGAGAAUUCUUUUUUUCUUUAAAAGAGAAUGCUUCUUAAUUUUUACGGAAACAAUUUUAUAGUAGGAAAAUUAUUCUGAGGACAUUUUCUGAAAGUGUGUCCCUUUUAUUACUUGAGGAAGCUUUGCAAUGAGCUUGCUGUUCUUUCUCUCUGCAAAAUCCUUAGCUGAUUAAAAACAAAACAAAACAAUCACCAGAGGCAUGUCUUAUCCUAAAUAACUUUCUAUGCAAGUGUCACUGAAGCAAAAUUAAUAGAUAAAAUGAAUCAUCAUGUGUCUCUUCAAAAAUGUUUAAUUCAAGCUUGUUACUAGGAAUCGCAGGAAGGAUGAGAAAACCUCGGUAAAUUCCACAGGUCCUGAGAAAAUGGAGCCUUCUGUGAAUAUACAAUAUAAAAUUUCAUGUGAUGGCUUUUAAUAUUGACAAUACAGUAAAAGGCUUAGGAAAACUAUUUUUGCAGGUUGUAGACUCUUUUAGCAUUAAUUUAGAAUGAAUGAUUUGUGUGCAUUUAAGCCCUGUUAUUUAACUUACUCCUCUUGAUAAAUCUCAUGUUGUUCAAUAUUUGCAUUAUUUUAUUCAGCAAACUUUAAGCUUAUGUGAUAAUUAAACAAUGGUUUGUCUCUACUUGUUAACUUACAUGGAGCCAUUUUUAUUUUAAAGCACAGAAACCUAAUUUUGAAAGAUUAAACAUUGCUGUAAAAAAUAGCAUCUUAACAGUCAUGUUUCAUGGGUAGUUUAAUUUAUCAGUCAAACACAUCUAGAUAAGAAUUCCAUCAGAGCAUUUAUAUUGUUGAUAAUAUCUCUAGGCAAUUUUUUUUUAGCAACUUUACUAGGUGCUUGUAUCUCCUAAUAUGGUCCUUUAUAUUGCCUUAGGGAAAAAAGGGACAAGUUCUAAGUAUGUAGAAUAAAUAACACACUUGCAGUAAAAACAUACAAAAAAACUGAACUCCCAGUCACUUAAUUCUUUACUUUAAUUCAUAAAUACAGGUCAUUUAACGGUGGUAGAACCUCAUUAAAAUUGAACUUUCAAGAAUUAUGACUGACUUCAGUACACUGGCCAUCGAUUAAUACCUGUUGAUUAUAAUAAUAAAAUAAAAGUCUUUCAAUGAGGUACAUGUGACAGCGUUGCAGCUAUGAGUGGAAUUUUAAAGGGGAAGUUUGAAGAAGUCAACGGCUCCUCACCCUGCUCUUCAGUGCAGGAAUCAGAUGAUGAAGUUUUCAGCUGUGACAGUACUGAGAGUGUUGAUAGUGUCAAUCGUUCAGUUUUAAUGAUUUUACCAGAAAAAAUGAGGAAAUAUCAACAGACUGAAAAUAUGUUUUCAGAGGCAUAGAAUCUUCAGGAAAAUACUGGAGUUCCUGAGAUCUCAAGGUACAUGUGACAGCACUGCAGCGAUGAGUGGAAUUUUAAAGAGGAAGUUUGAAGAAGUUGACGGCUCCUCACCCUGCUCCUCUGUGAGGGAAUCAGAUGAUGAAGUUUCCAGCAGUGAAAGUGCUGACAGUGGGGACAGUGUCAAUCCAUCCACUUCUAGUCAUUUUACCCCUUCCUCCAUUCUCAAAAGGGAGAAACGACUGAGGACAAAGAAUGUACAUUUUAGUUGUGUCACCGUGUACUACUUCACCAGGAGGCAAGGCUUCACAAGUGUGCCCAGUCAAGGGGGAAGCACCCUGGGGAUGUCCAGCCGCCAUAACAGCGUGCGCCAGUACACUCUUGGCGAGUUUGCAAGGGAGCAGGAGAGGCUCCACCGGGAGAUGUUGAGAGAACACCUUAGGGAGGAAAAGCUGAACUCCUUAAAACUAAAGAUGACUAAGAAUGGCACAGUAGAAUCAGAAGAAGCCAGCACUCUUACACUGGAUGACAUUUCUGAUGAUGACAUUGACCUGGACAACACAGAGGUAGAUGAGUACUUCUUCCUACAACCUUUGCCAACAAAAAAACGAAGAGCUCUGCUGCGUGCCUCUGGAGUGAAAAAGAUUGACGUGGAAGAAAAGCACGAACUCCGAGCCAUCCGCCUCUCACGAGAGGACUGUGGCUGUGACUGCCGAGUGUUCUGUGAUCCAGACACGUGCACCUGCAGCCUGGCUGGCAUUAAGUGCCAGGUGGAUCGUAUGUCUUUCCCAUGCGGCUGCACUAAAGAAGGAUGUAGUAACACAGCAGGUAGAAUUGAAUUUAAUCCUAUCCGUGUUCGGACUCACUUUUUGCACACAAUAAUGAAACUUGAACUGGAGAAAAACCGAGAGCAGCAAAUCCCCACGCUGAAUGGCUGCCACAGUGAGAUAAGUGCUCACAGUAGUUCUAUGGGCCCUGUCGCUCACUCCGUAGAAUAUUCAAUCGCAGACAGUUUUGAGAUUGAAACUGAGCCCCAGGCUGCAGUGCUGCACCUGCAGUCGGCUGAAGAAUUAGAUUGCCAAGGAGAGGAGGAGGAAGAAGAGGAGGAUGGGAGCAGCUUUUGCAGCGGAGUCACAGAUUCUAGCACGCAAAGCUUGGCACCUAGUGAGUCAGACGAGGAGGAGGAGGAAGAAGAAGAGGAAGAGGAGGAGGAGGAUGACGAUGAUGACAAAGGAGAUGGCUUCGUGGAAGGUUUGGGCACCCAUGCCGAAGUUGUCCCUCUUCCUUCAGUUCUUUGUUAUUCUGAUGGCACCGCCGUUCACGAAAGCCAUGCAAAGAAUGCUUCUUUUUAUGCCAACUCUUCAACUCUGUAUUACCAAAUAGAUAGCCACAUUCCAGGAACUCCAAAUCAGAUCUCUGAGAACUAUUCUGAAAGAGACACUGUCAAAAAUGGUACCCUUUCGCUGGUGCCUUACACCAUGACCCCGGAGCAAUUCGUUGACUAUGCCCGACAAGCAGAAGAGGCCUAUGGUGCCUCCCACUACCCAGCUGCCAACCCCUCUGUAAUCGUUUGCUGCUCCUCUUCCGAAAAUGAUAGCGGUGUGCCCUGCAAUAGUUUAUAUCCUGAACACAGGUCCAAUCACCCUCAAGUGGAAUUUCACUCAUACUUGAAAGGCCCCUCCCAAGAAGGGUUUGUCUCUGCAUUGAAUGGUGACAGUCACAUUUCAGAGCAUCCUGCUGAAAAUUCUUUGAGCCUUGCAGAAAAGAGCAUAUUGCAUGAAGAGUGCAUCAAAUCACCCGUGGUUGAGACAGUCCCUGUUUAGUAGCUUAAAUUAUUCUAGGACCAACUCUUCUCUUAUUUAAGGCACUGUAUUUAAUUGGAUUUCCUGGGCUCAUCAUUGUUUAAACUGAAGACCAAGAAAACUUGGACGGUGGUUAAUCUUCCAGACUGUAUUUUGUUUUUUCCUUUCUAGCCACAUGACUGUGGCAUUGCACAAAUACAGUCUCUGUAGGGAUUUUAAAAGAUUUCAGACUGUUUUGAUAGAAAAAGCUAAAUUUUAAAAUGCAUAUCUCACAGUUGCCUACCUGUCAAACUGUGUGAAACCUGCCAAUCUGUGUAGAUCAGAGCUCCAAAUUUUGGAUUAUCGGGCCUGUGCAAGAUUGUUAACUAAGGCUGGGAAAUAAUAAGAUUUAGAGUCCUAAUUUUCAAUAUAUCUGAAGAUAAUGAUGACUUUUUAAUGUAAAAGUAAUUAUUGUAAGAAAAAGAUUUAAUUGUUCCAUGUGUAUUUUAUUUAUGGUAGUUUAGAAGACAUGUUUUGAUGAAAAUGAACAGCCGCAUGUUCAUUCAAGCUGAAGAUGCAUAGCUAGUUCCACAGAGCAUGCCCACAUGGAUUGCAUCUGGAAUCCAUUCACAUUUUUAUGAUCAUGACUGAUCAGAUUUGCAAAUUCUUAAGGGUGAAAUAGGCCUAUUUUUGCUAUUUUGGACAAAUAAAUGAUUCUAUAUGUGCAGGUCCUUACACAGUUUUCUCUAAAGUUAAGAGUUAGGACAAUCCUCUGGGGAGAGUCUAGUUCACUGCCCUCCCUCAGCUGACUCCAGAGAUGGAGGUAGAAGGAAUUGCCUUUCUUUUUUAAACAGCAUCAUCUUGAUUCUUAGCUUGGACAGCACCUUUAAGCUCUACCCCCUACAUCAAAAUGCACUUUAGUGCCCCUUCACGGUACCUCGUGUGGGGUGGGGACUGAGAACUCUUUGAGAUGAAAAAAUUUAAAAAAAAAUUAAAAAGAUCUUUAACUAUUAUAAGGUUCAUAUAAUUAAUAUAGAGGAAUCAUCCAAUGAUACUUAUGAAGGGAAAAUGACCUAUUUUCCUUCACCACUCUGAGGACCUAACUCAGUAAAUGCAGAGGAGGCUGAGGAAACAUGGAAGAGACACGACCUCAGCAACCAGCCUUUUCUCCAGCGUGAUCAAUCCAUCUCUACAAAAUCAGUGUAUAAUGAGAUUUCCACUUAGUGACUAGCUGAUUGAAGGGGGGCCUCUACCCAAAUACUCAACUAGGCCUUUCUUUUCUGAAGCAUUUUGAUUUGUCUUGCCUGGGACAACUAGCAGAACAGUCCAGAAUGCAUUGCAUACUUUCUAAUUACCUCACAUUCUCUUAUUAAAGAGAACAGAUAGAAAUAAAACAUGCACUCCCCACCUUUAGAUUACCUGCACUUGGUUCGUCGGAGGACUUCUAGGAUCCCGUUUCCCUGUAAAUUAAUUUAGGUAACUAAAUAGUGUAAUUCUGCCUUUUUUUUUCCAAUGCAAUAUGACUAUGCUAAACCUGUUUCAUAUUUUUGACCUUCUAUUGUUAUAUCACUUCACAUGUUUUAUAACUAUUUGAAAUGCGGACAUGACUUGCUAUUCAGUGACUGCAUCGCUACUUAUUUUUUAUGUCUUUUAGACUUGGGUGUUUAGAAUUAUGGAUAUAAAUAUAUUGUAGAUCUCAAUUUCUAAAAAAAAUAUUUUAUUUAAUUGAACUUAAAAAUGCUUGAUCUAGAGAAAGUCCUCCAGUGGAAAAGUUUCUACUAAACUUUGUUUUGGGGAAAAAAUGUUUACUUGGCAGCUCUUCCACUGUGCAGUUGGUUUCUGCCCCUUCUCUUCCCCCCUACAUUGGGCCAAAUUUAUAACUCUUAAUAUUAACAUUAAAAGAGCUUUGGGUUUGUCUUUAUGUAGGUUGCAGUAAUGAGAGCAGGGUUGUUCCUUUUGAAUGAUUGGCCCUUUGGGCUAAUCAGAAUGAGGAUUUGUUGAAAUCUCAAAUAUACAUAUAUAUAUAUAUAUAUAUAUAUAUAUAUAUAUACACACACACACACACAUACACAUAUAUAUACACAUAUAUGUAUGUGUGUGUGUGUGUGUGUGUGUGUGUAUAUAUAUAUAUCCCAUGUUGUCUGCAAAGUGACAGUUUUUAGUGCUUAAUCUCCAAAAUUUUCCCCCUACUGAUACAAUCUAAAGAGCACAGGCCCAAAGAGAAAAUGACAAGAGGCUAUUGUUCCUUCAUUCAAGCACAUGAAAGGAUCAUGUGUACUGUAUUUGCUGGACCAUUACAAGCUCUUGAAGGAUCUGCUUGUGAAGUACUCUGAGGUUAUUCUUGGAACACAGAGUGUGGGAGAGUGGGGAAGAGCCAGCUCCAGCCUGAGCAAAGCUGAAGGGUAGAAUGACAGUCCAGUUUCUGAAAAGAGAUAUUUUAAUUUUAGUUCAGCUUUAUUUUCCUAAGACGAUAUGAAGCCUACUUUUUUAUUUUUGGCUAGGUCUUUGUUUUCUAGCUUUGUUUCCAAAAGGAUGCUUAAGAAAACAGAGUUUUUUUCCCCUAUCCAUUUAUCUAGGGUAGAAAGUCACUGCCCUGUGAGAAGAAUUACCCUUCCAAUCAUGACAGCUUCUAUUCCAACUUUUCAUAUACCUGACUAACCUGUAAACAUAUCCCACAAACCACAUACACAGGCUACCUAUUAAAACUCUCCCAUAUACCUAACACAUACACAUGCACACACAUACAAAAUAUAUACAUAUCACACACUUAGAGAAUGACAGAUUUCAGGCAAUGGCCAAUAGUCAGUAUUGAGUUUUUCUAACCCCAGAAUCUGGUUGGGCUUUAUGAUCUAAAAAAAUGUGGUUUAGAAAAGAGGAUAAUUGGUAGAGCUGUAGUUUGAAAAUAUCAGGUCAAAGUUGCAAACAUACUUAUGAUGGAAUCAUUUCAUUUUUAGUUCCUUUCCCAGAAAAGCUGAGAGAGCACACUGUUCCAGCUGACUUUUUUUUCCAUUAAUAGCCGUUCUAUUCAACAAAGAGCUGCCCACAUGCCAGGAAAGUGCUACAGUCCUUCUAAGCUUUUAAAAAUGGGGAUCAAGCUACAUGCAGCCAGUUGGAAUACUUAAGAUCUUUAUGCCAAGACACAAUAACCUGACCUGCAGCUGUUGUAUUGCCUCCAUAGUAUAUCUAGCCAAACUGUAGUCUUUGACACACAACUUUUUAGUCAUUCACUAUCAAUUGCAAAGCUUCAUGCUCCAGCCCUGGCUAUUCUAGUACCAGUCCUAUACCUUUAAAUGGGACUUAAUUCCCAGUUAUAAUCCUGGCCGAAUUGAUUUGAAAGUCAAGUGGCUGAAGCAGCUUGCAUCUCCUUUGUCAUUCCCAAUUUCCUUUGGGAGAAGUCAAUGAAAGAGAUUUACUUAAGUUUUUCCUCCUUAUCUCUUGAUCAUUAAUUAUUAAGACAUGGGUAAAAUUCAUUUGUCUCAUGUCUUUUGGUUGAUUGAAUAAUAUAGUUACUUUUUGAAAGCCCAUCAUUUCUUUGUGAUAAAACCAUUUUCUCAAUGUGACAGCCACAUGUAAAAUGUGAAACUAAUGUUUCUUAGUAUGUUUAAAAUCUUCACAAUCAUAUAUGGCCCUGCAAUACUCCCUGAAUUCCUUCCCUCCAAAAAAAAACUAUGAGUUGCAAAAACACUAGUUACGAAUUAAUCAAGAAGCAAAGAGAGUAUGUUAAGUGGCUAUGUUCUUUAAAAUUUUACAUUCUAAUAGAUGACUUCUAGGCAAAAUUUUGGUAUGAUUACCAUUAAACAGGAAAACAUACCAUGAUUUACUUUCUAUAACUUGCUAAUCACUGUUUCUUUUAUUUCAAUUUUUGAUAUUGUUGCACAAGUUUAUGACUCUUUGGUCUUUAUAUUCAAAAUUUAUUAAGUAUCAAUUCUUUCUUUCAACAAAUAUGUACUGAACACAUGCUGUGUUAGAACAACUGUCUUGGGUAGUAAAAAGAGGGGAACACUACAAAUUAUAAUGGAUAAUAUUAAUGAAGGGUGGCAUGAAAUAAUCAAGCUUUCUCAAAUCCUCUUAAUAUGUGAUUUUAUCAAGUGACAUUAGAAAAACUGACAUCAGUUCUUGUCUAAUUAUAUGUGAGCUGCAACUAAAAGAUGCUUCCUUUACCUAAAUUAUAGAACUCACUGGAUCGCCCUUCAUCUCUCUCCCUCCAUCUGAAAUGUAUGAAUUAAAUCAGGACUCAGCUAGGACUGAAUCAAAUGAAAAAGAAAUUUUCGAUUAAUUGCUUCUUCAAUGUUAGACCUAUAUAAGUGAUGCUAAAUUUACACCAGCAAACUCCUAUCAGACAGUUUCAAGGAGGAUUUGACUCAUGCAUAACCCAGGAAACAUUUCAGGAAACUUUUAAGACAACAGUGUGGAACACAAUCACUCUUACUUCUAUUUAUAAAAAGCCUAUCAAAACAGCAAAAUCCUGUUGCAAAUUCCAAAGACAUCACUUUGCAGCAGGUGGAAAACAGAGAGGUUGUUAGACUCCAUCACUUUCAGCUGGAGUUACAAACCAUCAAAUUAGCAGGUGGAAAAUUUAUAUUCUCAGAAGCCAACAGGAGACUGCCUUUUUAAAAGGUGUCAUGAAGCCUUCUAUUUCUCCAAACAACUCAAUAUUUCUCUUUAAAAUGGCAUCUCUGUUCCUUAUUCUCUUGAUGACAGUUUGCAGUGCCAUUAUAGCCAGUGUAUUAAAUACCAGGCUUUAAUGGGAAGCACCUUUGUGCUUUCAAAGGCAAGACUUGUCUGUAAUUUUAAAUUAGAACUGUUGGUUGUAUUCUUACCACAACCAAAACCCAAAGUUUAAAGGCUUGAUUACUCUAUAUUAGGUCUAAUAUGAAUUUUCACCUUCUGAUUGCAUUACUUUUUCUGAAAUCUGCUAACUAGUGCUGGAAUAACAAAAAUGCCUAAGCCAAAAUGCUGUAGCUCUGCACCAACAGCACAGCUCAUCAGAUGUUUUCUAUAGUAGUAAAGAAUUUGAUUGACUUAAUUGAAUAUCAGCAAUUUUAAUACCCACUAGAAUUAUGGAAGUAUCAGAGUGGAAGUGAGGACGCAAUAAAAGCUUAAUAAGUGGUGGUGUCUUCUAGGAAUUAUGAAAAAAAAAGCUCAGCAGAGCUAAGCCAGAUCUUAUUACAUCAUAAAGACUAGAGUUACAAAUGGCAGCCCCAAACCUAGAAGGGGCAGUUACAAUGUGGACACCCUUUCAGCCCAGUUGGUGCUCACAUCUGCUGACCAACAUUCAUAUCAAUUACAUUUUUACAGUCUGUAAGUCAUUUGAUGCUUUAGAAAAUAAAAACACACACCUACAGCAUUCUAAAGAAACUAUUUUGUUAAAAAAUUUAAACACAUUUUAUAUUAAAAUAAGUGAUCAAUGACUUUCAUGAUUGUCAAAAGUAAAAAGUGCAGACAUUUAAAAAAGCUCUUCUUUCACAUUUUACCUACCAAAUCUAGAUAUUCAACGUGAGUCCUUAAAACAGUCACUUCUAAAUUUUAUUUUGACUCCUUUCUUGGCUUUUUCAAACUGGACCAUGAGACCCCCUUCCUAAACAAUGCAGUUGUUUUGUUUUAUUCUUUUUUUCCAGAAAUUCAAGCUGAAACAUUUGAUAUGACCUGUGUUUUACCUGGUGAUCAGUUCUCAGGCUAGUCUAAGUCUGUGCUGUCUUGGCAUGCCUUGGGUUUCCUAUCCUGAGAGUGGUAAUGCCAGUAGAAUGAUGGGAACCAGGAGAGUGAAUACGACCAGAUUCAAAGCCUAAAACAAUAUGUUUCAGUUUACUUUUAUAUGUAGAUUUUUUAAAUAUUCACAUCUAGCCUGGAAUUUUAGUAAAUACAGAUACUUGUUGUAUCCAUGGGAAAUGAGGUCAUUUCAAAGAUGUAAGUCACGUUGGUGACUACUUUCUUUUACUUGUGAUAAAUAUAUCACUAUACAGGGUAAUUGCUUUUAUAAAUUUGAUCCUUUGCAUUGGCUUAUAAUUCAAGAAAUGUCAACUUCACUGUGUCACUUUAUGUCAUCUCUCAUAAAAGUUUCUGGCAGGACUAAAGUUUCAAAGGAAUGUGAUAGAAUUUAUUUUGGAUAACAUUUGUAUUCAGCAUGCUAAUGAUGUAACUCCUCUCUUUAUCAUUACCACGGUGAUAGUUAAGUUCAUUCGUUAACUCAUUUUAGUGACAUGUGAGGCCAUUUAAAUAUUUUUAAGAUAAUGUAUAUUGAUUAGAAAGGGUUAGAAGGAGACAAAUUUAUGGUAGAAAUUAGCCUUGCCAUUGUCUAAGUUAAUUUAUGUGACCUGAUUGAACAGUUUUAGUUGUAACUUUAGAGUAGCUUCUUUGUUAGAGGAUCUCUUUCCUUUCUCUUUUGGUUUUCUCCCAAUAUUUUUAUCUGUCUUGGGAUUAUCUUAAAAGGUAUUUAUUAAUGAGUAUUUGGAAGAAAAUUGACCUAGAAAAUGUCUCUUUUAAAUUUAUCUAGGUACUUGUAUCACCAGAGACCUUCAUCAAGUCCUACUGCCACACUGGAUAAGGCCACUACCCCCGACCCUUCUUGUCAGGGACAUGGCUUCCUAAUAAUGGUUUUGCUGUUGUCUCUACAUAGGGGACCUAUGGAAAAGGAGUUUGAAAUUUCUACCUUUGUAGUACAUUGUAUCCAAUUUUGUUUUGCUCCUCCUUUUCAUGUGGUCACCAAGCUUUUUUCCUUAGCCAUUAAAAAAGCCACCCCUCUUUAAAACAAAUUUAAAGAUCUAUAUACAUUUUUGCAACUUUAUUUAAUAAAAAAGAGAAGAAAAAAUAAAAUCUAAAUCUCAAUUACCCUAAAGUGGAAAAACCUAAGUAUCUAACCUAGGAACUUGUUGCCUGGUGGUGGUUGUUGUUGUUGUUGUUUUUUAAUUUAUUUAGUGUUGAUCCUUGAGUUAUUUAAUGGUAUCCAAAUGAUAUCUGAAAGUGAUUGAUUUUAAGAUGUAAUAGUUGGCAAAGUCAUUUCAUUUGUGUCUCAAACAAAUAAAGCCCACUGCCAUGGGUUACCAUCUGAACCCUGAUUCAUUAGGCACUAGUCAUGCCAAAUGGGGAUCUCAGAAUAGUUUAAUCUUUUCAAAGAUACUCACAAUGGCCAACUGUGUGUGAAUACUGGAAAGUUUGAGAUUCUUCUAUAUUCUUCAAAUUUAUGGUCCUGAGACUAGGAGGGAUCUCCAGAGGUCAUAUGGCUCAUCGAUCUACCACCAGGGAAGACUGUCACUUAGGCAUGCCCAACAGGAGAGAUCGCCAUCUAUUCUUAACAUCUCUAGGGAAGGCAGUUUCCUUGGCAACACAAUUCAGCUCUCUUAGGUUUUCUCACAAUAAGAAAAUAUCUUGGCCAGUCUUUGAGGGUUAGGCACCUGGCAACAGUUGUGGUGAUUUGGGCCAUUGUACUAGGGGAUUCAAGGGAAGUUGGGUUUCCCCCUACAUUUGGUGAUUAUUACAUUAAUAUAUGAUCAUUCCAUAAGUCUCCUAAGAAAUCAGAUUUUUAAAGAAAGACACGGAUUCAGAGACAAUGGUCUGUAACAUGACCAACUUUUGACAAAUAUGGCUGUACUAGGUUUUCAUUUUUGCUGUUGUUGUUGUUUGUUUUUGUGAUUGCUCUUAUGUCGGUAGGUAAUGUCAGGAAAAGUGACUGUUUCAGAUCCCCAGUACAAACAUCAGAACUAGGAUCAAAUGACUUGACUUUUAAGCUGUUCCAUUUUCUAAGAAGUUACAAUUACAAAAAGUAAGCAUUUUCUACAUUCUUACUUCUAAGUAAUGACCUUCUCAUUAAUCUUUCCUUGGCUUAAAAUGACAAAUAAGAAUCCAAAGUUUUUCCACUCCUCCUGUGGGAGAUAGGAAUAGUUGUGAAGAGUCUGAUGGAAUAAAAUGACUCCAGAGAUUUACACAGCCACCAUUUGAUCCCAGCCUUUGUCCUUGUGUUAUUUAAACAAUGGCUUCCUGCUUUCUCAGGGGUCAGGAAAAUGAUUUAAAAAUUUGUCUUCUUGACAAGGCCUGAAAACGAAGGGAGGUGUCGUGGAGAAAUGGUGAUUUUUCUGGUUACAUCACUUGAUUCAAGCACUCCCUGGAGCUUUCAAAGCCUUUUUUAUCUGCUCAGAGUUGACACCCAACUCAGAGUCAGAACUCACCAGAAGAUGAGGAACACCCCCGAAAUCAAUGUUUCCUUUCUCCAUGGGAUUUUUUUCAAUCUUGGUACAGCUGCAUAUCUCCCAAACUCGGAUGCUCUUGUGAAAUGACAGCCACAUCAGUGUGGUUACUCCCCACAAAUAACACUAGGGGGAAAUGACCUUUUUUAUUUAAAAAAAAAAAAAAGGCUAAUGCUAUAGAAUGAUCAUGUAAAGAAUGUUGAAUAAAAUUUGGCCCAUGUUUUAAUUGACUCUAGGCACCUCUAUUGAAAUAAGUCUGAGGCAUAGUUUGUGAAACAUGUUUCAAAAGUGUUUGAUGUAUAAUAAAUGCUAGAAAUUUACAGUACAGAAAUAGUAAAAAAAUAAAAUAAAAAUAAACCUGUAGAUUACAGCUCUGUUCCUAAGAACCUCAGCCUUUAUUGUGUCUUAGUAAAGUUGAUCUGCUUUAUUUUUAGUUUAUUGAAUUUCUGGUGUACUAGCCUCUUAAGAUAGAACUUUUAAUACAUAUGUACUGGUUAAUGCCUGUUUACGCAGAAAAUGGCACUUUGUUCUUUCAGUGUGUUUCCCUCAGUGUCACAGGGUAUAUCAAUUUGAUAGAUCAUUUGACAUUUGUCAAAAAUACGUUUCCCAUUUUAAAAAUAUGUAUAAUUGGUUGCAUAGACAUAUGUCACUUUUUGCAGUGUCUUCAUCUUGAUCAUAGUUUUAGACAUCAACUAUGUCUCACUUUCCAACUGCCAUAGAAAUUUGGUACAUUUGCAAAUUCUGGUGGAAUCUAGUGAGCUGAAUGUAUUGGUAGAUCAAAUGAUCCAAAGGACUUGGGUGUUAUCCUUCAGUCUGUGUUGAACCAUUCAGAUAUUGGGAAUGGUCCUUACACAAGGGAAGUCUUUUGAGAAUAUUUGUUCUCUUAUUUUUUGUUUGUUUGUUGCUGGCAAAAAAAAAAGUAACUUUAAAAACUCAGAAAAGCCACUGAACUGUAUUUUGUGACCUUAUGAUUAGUUUUAUCUUUCAACUGAUUUUUAUUGUUACUUUUACUCAAUAUCAACAGUACUUCAAUAGAUAUUUAUUAGUUAUGUUCAAUCUAAUGACUUAAAACAGUUGAAAAGGAGGAAAAUCAACUCCAGUCCACACAUACAGUCAUGUUACAUUAAGAUGUCAUGUUGUAUGUCACACAGUUUCUAGAUUGAUUUCUCUUGUGUAUAAGUUAUAACAUCAAAAAUGCCAAAGGGUAUAUAAAAUAAGCUACAAUAAUAUUCAACAGAACUUAACCUGGACCUUAUGUUGUAAUAAUUUAUUCAUAUUAGCUGUAGUCUUCUGUAUUUAUAUUUUCAGUAUUUAUUAUGAAUGACAUGGAAAUUCGUGUAUUUAUUGUGGCUUUUUAUUGCAGUGUGUAUAUAUAUAUAACAAAUAAGCAUUUUUAAGUCUUAUCCUUAAGUUUCUUUUAUUAGUGGCACUUGUAUUAUGCUGUACUUUUUAUUACAUAUUGUACAAUAUCUUGUCCAUUUGUUUGCAGCAGAGUAAAACCGGUUUCUAAGUUGUA